AAACAGAUGGAAAUGUCUGAGUCUUUGCAGGUGAGCAACUGAAAUUUGCUUUCUGUAAGAAGUUCAAUAGAAUGAAAUAUUUAUCAUUUUGUGUAUUCUAUGUGGCUUAGGCAAGGUUAGGAGUUAGUGCAUAAUAUAAUUUUUGCUCAGAAGAAAAUGAAGUGUUUCAUAUUUAAAGCUAUUCAGUCUUAACUACUUUCCUUUUCAUUAUCAAUUAUUAUCAUGUUUCUAAAAAUAAAAAGAUAUGUAAUAACUAGAUUGACUAUUAUUAGGAAACAGUUGAAGAGAUGAACGUUCAAAGAAUGCUGAUGAUUUUUGUGUCAAGAAGGUGAAUGAGUCAUUGUAUAAAAAGGUAUAAAAGAAAUACGGAUCACAGAUUAGAAAGUUUCUCUUUUUUUAGAAGAAACAGUAGAGUGCUUUGUGCCAAAAGCUGAUUAUCACUAAUGCUUCAUAUAAAAUUGGAUACAAAAAAGCAACAGUUUUAUGCUUUGAGCUAAUUUGUCACCUUGGAUGUCACAGGAUAUGAAACCCACAACUUUCACAAAAGCAACAGUCCAUUUUCACUGCCUUUUCAAAUGUUUGGGCAUUGCAAUUGAAAUGAUUUUAUUACUAUUUAGAAAUUUAAAAAGAUUUCACCAUUUUCCUAGUGUUUUUUGUUUGUUUGUUUGUUUGGUUUGAUUUUUCUGGGACAGGGUCUCGCUCUGUCACCCAGGCUGGAGUGCAGUAGUGUCAUCUCAGCUGACUGCAACCUCUACCUCCCAGGCUCAAGCAGUCUCCCACCUCAGCCUCCCAAAGUGUUGAGAUUACAGGUGUGAGCCACUGUGCCUGGCCAAGGUUUUUUUUUUAAGUAAGAAUGAAAACCCAAACCAGUGCAAAAAAAUUAUUUUUGGUGAACCUGAAUGCCAGAACUUAAGUUCAAAGAAAUCGAGAUGAUUUUUUAAAAAACAAUCUGCAAUCACAAGUUCUUUAAAAAUCAAACAGAAGUGCCCUCACAAAAUCAUGUCUUGUUUAUGAUGAAAUGGAUACUUCCUUUAUCUGAUGUCAAGUGACUAACUUGUUGUUUCCCUCAGAAAGCCUCUUGACUAAGGUUUCCACUUGCCUUUAUAUUUACUUAGCAAAAGGUGUCUGUGACUAUUCACUUUCAGAGAAAGAAGAAAAGCAGAAAAGAGAAUGCACGUCUUAAGAUGCUAAGGGACAGGGUAUUGAAAUAGCCUGGAAAGUGUUCAGAAAGAAUGCCAGCAAAUCAAAUGUUCACCUGGAGCUCGGGAAGAAAAGAAAAAUCAAUGUGCAAAGAGUGGUCUUAUUUUGCUAGAAAGUGACUCUCCAGAAAAGCUGCAAGGAAGCUCUCCCUUAACAACACCUCUGACGUUCCAGAGACUGUCCUAAACUCCAGUGUUCAGCUUCUGUCUGGAAAUCAGACUUAUCUUCGAGUCUUCCUUCAUACAGGAAAAAUGCAUGUGGCAGAGAGACUGCUGGAUCCGUCGCUUCCCAGGUCUUCUAAUCAAUCUGGAGGAGUCUCAGAAGCUGGGAGCCCAGUUCUUGAAGUAUUAUUCUGAAAGCACUGGCCAGAAGUGCAGUAGGAGCUGCUGUCUUCGGAAGGAUGUUUCCUGUAACCUGGCUGUCUUCUACCACAGUCCUAUUCAUGACAAUAUCAACUGCCUCCAUGUUCACUGCCCAACACUGGAGAGCUGCAUAUUAGAGCCUGGAACCAGUGCCAUUUUGUACAACAUAACAGACGGUAUAGAUCCGGAUUUGCUGGUUUUUGAACAAUCUCCCACAUAUCUAAAUACUCGUUCUUCAUCCAAUAGAUGGGACAGACUAAGGAUUCUAAAAGCUAUGAAUUUAGAUAAACAAACCACCACGAUAAAUGGUAUGCUGCCAUCCACAGAGGCUCCAUCCUCAACCACGCAUCAAGAUUUGGUUGUAAACACAAACAGUACCAGUUAUUCUAAGGAAUUAACCACAGAUUUUUGGGCAAGAUUUACUUCCCUGAAUGAGUCCAUUACCACAAAGAUAAAUAAGGUGUCACCAAGUACUGAUUUCAUCAGCAAUCCAGAUAAUAAGACUAUUUCUCCUUUCUUUGAACCCAUAGACACAAAACUUUCUCAUAUGCCUGUUCCACCUGGACUCAACAGUAGCAAACAAUUACUAAACAAAACCAAAGGAUACAAUAGCAGAAACCACACAUCUGCAAAUGAAGAUGAGGUAUCUGUGACUUCAAAGACUUGGCUGGUUUCUGUGGCCCUUUGCACCUCUGUCAUCUUUCUCGGCUGUUGUAUAGUCAUCCUGGCAUCUGGAUGCUGUGGAAAGCAGCAGGGCCAGUAUAAACCAGGACAGAGAAAAUCAGGAUCCUUGCAAAUUAAAAACCGUAACCAUAUGAAGGAGAACUCUUCAUAGUAAAAACUGUAGCAAGAUUAUAUGCUUUCAAGGAUAUCAUUUUUAGUUUUGUGUAAGAAAACGCAGUUUGGUUAAAAAAAAAAAAUAGGCUGGGCGUGGUGGUUCAUGCCUGUAAUCCCAAAACUUUGGGAAGCCAAGGCAGUAGAUUUGCUUGAGCCCAGGAGUUCGAGACCAGCCUGGGCAACAUAGUGAGACUCUGUCUCUAUAAAAUGAAAAAUAAUUUAAAAAAAGCACAUGGGGCGAUAUGAUGCACCUGUGGUCCCAGCUACUUAGGAGGCUGAGGUGGGAGGACUGCUUGAGCCCAGGAGGUC